AGAUUUAGCUAUUGCUUUUUCAGUGAUCCUGGCUCCUCUCAGUUAGAGUCAAGCCUCUGGAGGAAAUUGACCAGCUCUAGGCUGCCACCGUGAAUUUUUGUGCAGAAACCCUGGAGAAACCUCCAGAGAGCCAUAUAGAAACUGAAAGUGGAAAGGAGGCAGCCAGGUGGACCUAUGAUUUGCAUAAACUUUUUCUUUUUUCUCUUUGCUUCCUCCAGGCAGCUUGCCUGUCUUUUUCCCUCUCCAGAGGCCACCUCACCCCGCAGUACCCUCAGUUACUUCCUAGCCAGUUUUAUUCCCAGGAUUUUCUCUUCCUCUGCCAAUUAGCUGCUAAGCCAAGUUGUUGCUUAACAUUUCCGCUAACGAAAGUUACCUUGCUGAGAAAAGGUGAAAUGAUUGUCAUUUUUGGGGGAAUAAACAUUGUGAUUUAGAAACUCAGGUGCAUGUAAAUCUUUAGUGUUCAUAACUUUAACCCCUGCUGCUGGUGGAGAUUGCUGACCCUUGCUAGUUAAAGAGAAGAUAACUAUAAAUAGAGCCACCAAAAGUGAGAGGUAUGGCAAAGUAGCCUUUAGUCAUUCGGGGUGUUUGUAGAUUCUCAUUAUUUUUUUAAACACCUUUAUUGAGGUUGUACACCACAAAAUUCACCCAUCUUAAGUGUACGAUUCGAUGACUUUAAGUAAAUUUACAGAGUUGUGAGGCCAUUGUUGGAAUUCAGUGGUAGAACAGUUUCAUCACCCCGAAAAGAUCCCCAUGCCCAUCCAUUCCUCUCACUCUUUGUUUCCUUCUUCAGUCUCAGACUACCACCAAUAUGCUUUCUAAUCUAUAGAUUUGCCUUUUUUGGACAUUUGCCAUAAAUAGAAUCUCAUGUACUUUUCUGACAGUGUGGGGAAGAAAAAAAGCCUUUUUCUCAUGAACACAUAGCAAUGGAGGGGUCUGGUCUCAUUGCCAUCAACAUCUAGAAUGUAACAGGAGACAGAUGUGGCGGUGAAUCUUGGGAGAAUCAUUUAAUAUUGAAGUCUGUUUUCUGUAAACUAAUAAUCAGAUGAGAGCUGUGUGCGUAUAUGAGAACAUUCUGCAAGCCACACAGUGCUAUGUACAUGUUAUUAUGUAUCCUGAAACAUUUUUGGAUGAGCUUAUAUCUUUUAAGGAAUGGAGAGGAAGAAAAAGAAGUUUUGAGAAUUGCAUUCACUAUUAGGUAGGUGGACUGAUGAUGCUGGCCCAAGAUGGGAAGAGUUCUUGACCUUACUCAGCAGCCUGCUCUUAAGAUGGAACAGAUUAAAAGGGCCAAUAAACUGUUUACCAAUGAUUGUAUAUUUCUGAAGAAAACUUUGAACAUCCCAGUUAUAUCAGAGAAGCCUUUGUUGUUUAAUGGACUUAACUCCAUUGAUUCUCCAGAAAAUGAAACUGCUGAUAACAGUUUUUCUCAGGAAGAGGAGCCAGUGGUGGCCGGGGAAGACCUCCCUCCUCCCAGUCCUCAAGAAUCUGAUGUUCAGCCUGUGCAGCCUGAGGAAGUGUCAGCCAGAGAUUUCCUGCAGAGACUUGACUUGCAGAUUAAGUUAUCAACACAGGCAGCCAAGAAGCUAAAAGAAGAGAGCAGAGAUGAAGAAAGUCCCUAUGCAACUUCCCUCUAUCACAGUUAGGUGAUUUGGGGGCAUAACUCUAACCAAAAUUAAGAUAUGUUUGGACCAUAAAGAAUCCAACAACUGAAGAUUCAAAAACAUCCCUUCUGGAUUCCUAUAGUGUCCAUCUUAAAAUCAUAACUAGGUAGUUCUACCUGCUGCAGUUGCACUGAAGUGAUUAGUUCCCUCUGGCUUUCUAUAAUUUUAAGUCUUUAUUAUGGCAUGAUGGCAAGGUUGUAGCCUAAAGCUCAUCACUUUUGUAGGUGGUGUUAGUUUUUAGACUAGCUUUUAUAAAUACUAAUUGACAUAAAGCAUCAAAGAUUAUUUAUAUAUUUAGGCUAAAAAUAAUGUUUAUCUCCUUAUGCAAUCCUGAUUAUGUGAAAAUAUGGUUGCUGUUUAAGUGAUGCUGAAUUUGCUGUGUGUUUAUAACUUAAGUGCUAUAUAUAUAUUUCGAUAUGUCUUACAUAUUCUCUAUUAAUAUAAAGAACCAAAUUUUGUCUGCUAUUUUGUAAAAAUAAACUACAAAAGCCUGAAUGAGAAAAUAAACUAUGUUUUCAAACUUGAGUCUCCUUUUUUUUUUUAACAAAUGAGAAAAUAAAAUUGACUUUUAAAUUAUA